ACAGCGGGGCGUCACCUCGGACAUACGAACAGCGGGCGGUGUUCCCGGCUCCGUGGGGCCGUCUUCCCGGCGAGUCCGCGACGGUCGCCGCCCACGGCGAGGAACCCUUAACAUUCAGGGAUGUGGCCAUAGAAUUCUCUCCAGAAGAGUGGAAAUGCCUGGACCCUGCCCAGCAGAAUUUGUAUAGAGAUGUGAUGUUGGAGAACUACAGAAACCUGGUCUCCCUAGCUAUGUGUUCUCAUUUCACCCAAGACUUUUUGCCAGUGCAGGGGAUAGAAGAUUCAUUCCACAAACUUAUACUGAGAAGAUAUGAGAAAUGUGGGCAUGAUAAUUUACAAUUAAGGAAAGGCUGUAAAAGUAUGAACGUGUGUAAAGUGCAGAAGGGAGUUUAUAAUGGAAUUAAUAAAUGCUUGUCAAAUACUCAGAGCAAAAUAUUUCAAUGUAAUGCACGUGUCAAAGUUUUUAGUAAAUUUGCAAAUUCAAACAAAGAUAAGACAAGACAUACUGGAGAGAAACACUUUAAAUGUAACGAAUGUGGCAAGUCAUUUCAGAAGUUCUCAGACCUAACUCAACAUAAAGGAAUUCAUGCUGGAGAGAAACCCUACACUUGUGAAGAACGUGGCAAAGACUUUGGAUGGUACACAGACCUGAAUCAACACAAGAAAAUUCAUACUGGAGAGAAACCUUACAAAUGUGAAGAAUGUGGCAAAGCCUUUAAUAGGUCAACAAACCUUACUGCACAUAAGAGAAUUCACAACAGAGAGAAAGCUUACACAGGUGAAGAUCGUGACAGAGCCUUUGGAUGGUCCACAAACCUGAAUGAAUAUAAGAAAAUUCAUACUGGAGAUAAACCCUACAAAUGUAAAGAAUGUGGGAAAGCCUUUAUGCAUUCCUCACACCUGAAUAAACAUGAGAAAAUUCAUACUGGAGAGAAACCCUACAAAUGUAAGGAAUGUGGCAAAGUCAUUUCCUCAUCCUCAAGCUUUGCUAAACAUAAGAGGAUUCAUACUGGCGAGAAACCCUUUAAAUGUUUAGAAUGUGGUAAAGCCUUUAAUAUUUCCACAACCCUUACUAAACAUAGGAGAAUUCAUACUGGAGAGAAACCCUACACAUGUGAAGUAUGUGGCAAAGCCUUUAGACAGUCCGCAAACCUUUAUGUACAUAGGAGAAUUCAUACUGGAGAGAAACCCUACACAUGUGGAGAAUGUGGCAAAACCUUUAGACAGUCCGCAAACCUUUACGUACAUAGGAGAAUUCAUACUGGAGAGAAACCUUACAAAUGCGAAGACUGUGGCAAAGCCUUUGGACGGUACACAGCCCUGAAUCAACACAAGAAAAUUCAUACUGGAGAGAAACCUUACAAAUGUGAAGAGUGUGGCAAAGCCUUUAAUAGUUCAACAAACCUUACUGCACAUAAGAGAAUUCACACCAGAGAGAAACCCUACACAUGUGAAGAUCGUGGCAGAGCCUUUGGAUUGUCCACAAACCUGAAUGAAUAUAAGAAAAUUCAUACUGGAGAUAAACCCUACAAAUGUAAAGAAUGUGGGAAAGCCUUUAUACAUUCCUUGCACCUGAAUAAACAUGAGAAAAUUCAUACUGGAAAGAAACCCUACAAAUGUAAGCAAUGUGGCAAAGUCAUUACCUCAUCCUCAAGCUUUGCUAAACAUAAGAGGAUUCAUACUGGCGAGAAACCCUUUGAAUGUUUAGAAUGUGGUAAAGCGUUUACUAGUUCCACAACCCUUACUAAACAUAGGAGAAUUCAUACUGGAGAGAAACCCUACACAUGUGAAGUAUGUGGCAAAGCCUUUAGACAGUCCGCAAUCCUUUAUGUACAUAGGAGAAUUCAUACUGGAGAGAAACCCUACACAUGUGAAGAAUGUGGCAAAACCUUUAGACAGUCCGCAAACCUUUAUGUACAUAGGAGAAUUCAUACUGGAGAGAAACCUUACAAAUGUGAAGAGUGUGGCAAAGCCUUUGGACGGUACACAGACCUGAAUCAACACAAGAAAAUUCAUACUGGAGAGAAACUUUACAAAUGUGAAGAGUGUGGCAAAGACUUUGUAUGGUACACGGACCUGAAUCAACAGAAGAAAAUUUACACUGGGGAGAAACCUUACAAAUGUGAAGAGUGUGGCAAAGCCUUUGCCCCAUCAACAGACCUGAAUCAACACACGAAAAUUCUUACUGGAGAGCAAAGUUACAAAUGUGAAGAGUGUGGCAAAGCCUUUGGAUGGUCCAUAGCCCUGAAUCAACACAAGAAAAUUCAUACUGGAGAAAAACCUUACAAAUGUGAAGAGUGUGGCAAAGCCUUUAGUAGGUCAAGAAACCUUACUACACAUAGGAGAGUUCACACUAGGGAGAAACCCUACAAAUGUGAAGAUCGUGGCAGAUCCUUUGGAUGGUCCACAAACCUGAACGAAUAUAAGAAAAUUCAUACUGGAGAUAAACUCUACAAAUGUAAAGAAUGUGGGAAAGUGUUUAAACAGUCCUCACACCUGAAUAGACAUGAGAAAAUUCAUACUGGAAAGAAACCCUACAAAUGUAAGGAAUGUGGCAAAGUCAUUACGUCAUCCUCAAGCUUUGCUAAACAUAAGAGGAUUCAUACAGGUGAGAAACCCUUUAAAUGUUUAGAAUGUGGUAAAGCGUUUACUAGUUCCACAACCCUUACUAAACAUAGGAGAAUUCAUACUGGAGAGAAACCCUACACAUGUGAAGAAUGUGGCAAAGCCUUUAGACAGUCAGCAAUCCUUUAUGUACAUAGGAGAAUUCAUACUGGAGAGAAACCCUACACAUGUGGAGAAUGUGGCAAAACCUUUAGACAGUCUGCAAAUCUUUAUGCGCAUAAGAAAAUUCAUACUGGAGAGAAACCCUACACGUGUGGAGACUGUGGCAAAACCUUUAGACAGUCUGCAAAUCUUUAUGCACAUAAGAAAAUUCAUACUGGAGAUAAAACCAUACAAGUGUAAAGAAUGUGGCAAAGCCUUUAAGUCAUACUACAGCAUUCUUAAACAUAAGAGAACUCAUACCAGGGGAAUGUCUUACGAAGGUGACGAAUGUCGCGGUCUUUAAAUGCUCCUCAAUCCUUUCUAAUCAUAAGAUAAUUCAUAAUGAAGAGAAACUCUAAAAUGUGAAAAAUGUGAGAAGGCUUUUAAUCACACCUCAAUCUGUUGUAGACAUAAGAGUAAUUAUAUUGAUGAGAAGCCAAAUUAAAAUUAAAAAUGUGGCAAAGACUUCCAAUUCUAGUCAGUUCUUAAUGUAAUUCCUACUGAAGAAAACACCUGGAAAUACAAAAAAUGUGGCAAAACUUGUAACCAAUGCUUAGCAUUUUUGCACAUGAUAGUAUUUAUAUGUGAGACUACUUGUACAAACAUAAAAAUAUACAAAAGCUAUUGUCUACUUGAAAUUUAUAGUUAAUAAAAGCAUUAUAAAUGUAAUUUCUGUUGAAAGACCUUUUAGAAAAUAUAGGCCAUUAAAGUGAAGAAUAGUCUUAAGACAGAGAAUACAAAGAUAAAGAGGGCUCUAGUACCUGUACUUGUAUCCCAGAACUUACUAUAUGCAUUUUGUACUAGAGGAAAACUCUGAAGCAGUUGCUUAAACUUUGUUCAACAUCAGAGAAUUUAUAUUGGAGAGAAAUCCUACAAAUGUAAUAAAUGUGGAAAAACCUCUGUUCAGAAACUGCAGGUUAAGAAACCAGAGGCCAGGCGCGGUGGCUCACGCCUGUAAUCCCAACACUUUGGGAGGCCAAGGAGGGUGGAUCACCUGAGGUCGGGAGUUCAAGGACAGCCUGACCAAUAUGGAGAAACCUCGUCUGUACUAAAAAUACAAAAAUUAGCAGGACAUGGUGGUGCAUGGCUGUAAUCCCAGCUACUCAGGAGGCUGAGACAGGAGAAUGGCUUGAACCCAGGAGGUGGAGGUUGCGGUGAGCUGAGAUCGUGCCAUUGCACUCCAGCCUGGGUAACAAGAGUGAAACUCUGUCUCAAAACAAGAUAAAAAGAAAAGAAACACCAGAGAAUUUUUACUAGAAUAUAAUUUGUAGGUGCAGUAAAUGUGAAGAAAUAUUUAGGCUAAAAUUAAGACUAUGUAAACAUCAGAGGAUUUACAGUAGAAAGAACUAAGGAACUAACACUUCAGACUUUAAAAUAAAUCAGAGUAUUAAGUAUAACAAAAGUUGAACCUGUUAGAAAAUUUCCUUGUAUAUAAGUUGAAAAGUAGGUUUUUGAAGAGAUAUAUUCGAAAUAUAUUUUUUCACUUGAAAAAAGUAAAAAUUUUUUUCAAAAGCAAAUAAUUCAACUCUAAAAUUAUACUAUUUCAACAUUCUCAUUUAUGUGAAAGCAUGUGAUAAAUUGUUGCUGCGUCAGAGAUAUGAGAAACUCCUUUGCAUUAGGUGGGCAUUAUUCAUAGACUUCUACAUGAAAGAGAAGAGAAAUAAAAGAUGCACCAGGAAAAUCUGAGCAGAGAGGCUUUUAGUGGUUGACUUACUGAGUGAUGCCUGAAGUAGGUGUUCAGAGUAAUACUUUGCGUUAUACUGAGAGAGAAUCUGAAUUUUAGUAGUAAAUUGUUUUGCCAACUGUAUAUUUAUGUAAUAAGUGCAAUAAAAUGCAGUAAAUUUUAAAAUUCUCUUAAGAUAAUGUGUGAACUUAAUUUUUGAAAUAAAAAUUGUUAUUGUGUUAAAA